GUCAUUCCCCUGCGCUCUCUUUCCUCACCCUUCCCCCCGCCACCGUGGGUUCCAGACUUGGGAUAAGUAAACAGCGGGUGGAGCGAGGCCUACGGACCCAGGCCAGGUGGGAGUCUGCACUCUUCAAGGGGCCUGGGCUGCUGCUCACGGGUAUUAAAGAACUCCGCGUUGUUCAUGGCUGAGGCGAUGCAUUAGGAAGAUCCUGGACCUAGAGAACAAGUCCCCCGAACGCUGAGUUGGAGGCGGGACUUCGGGUGCGCGUUGGCGGGAGCAUGCUGGGGCUCUGCGGGCAGCGGCUCCCCGCGGCGUGGGUCCUGCUUCUGUUGCCUUUCCUGCCGCUGCUGCUGCUUGCAGCCCCCGCGCCCCACCGCGCGUCCUACAAGCCGGUCAUCGUGGUGCAUGGGCUCUUCGACAGCUCGUACAGCUUCCGCCACCUGCUGGAAUACAUCAAUGAGACACACCCCGGGACUGUGGUGACAGUGCUCGAUCUCUUCGAUGGGAGAGAGAGCUUGCGACCCCUGUGGGAACAGGUGCAAGGGUUCCGAGAGGCUGUGGUCCCCAUCAUGGCAAAGGCCCCUCAAGGGGUGCAUCUCAUCUGCUACUCGCAGGGGGGCCUUGUGUGCCGGGCUCUGCUUUCUGUCAUGGAUGAUCACAACGUGGAUUCUUUCAUCUCCCUCUCCUCUCCACAGAUGGGACAGUAUGGAGACACGGACUACUUGAAGUGGCUGUUCCCCACCUCCAUGCGGUCUAACCUCUAUCGGAUCUGCUAUAGCCCCUGGGGCCAGGAAUUCUCCAUCUGCAACUACUGGCAUGAUCCCCACCACGAUGACUUGUACCUCAAUGCCAGCAGCUUCCUGGCCCUGAUCAAUGGGGAAAGAGACCAUCCCAAUGCCACAGUAUGGCGGAAGAACUUUCUGCGUGUGGGCCACCUGGUGCUGAUUGGGGGCCCUGAUGAUGGUGUUAUUACUCCCUGGCAGUCCAGCUUCUUUGGUUUCUAUGAUGCAAAUGAGACCGUCCUGGAGAUGGAGGAGCAACUGGUUUAUCUGCGGGAUUCUUUUGGGUUGAAGACUCUAUUGGCCCGGGGGGCCAUAGUGAGGUGUCCAAUGGCCGGUAUCUCCCACACAGCCUGGCACUCCAACCGUACCCUUUAUGAGACCUGCAUUGAACCUUGGCUCUCCUGAGGAUAUAUUCAGGGGUCCCCAGGAACUCCUCGGUCCAGAGACCAAGUGGUGGCCUUGGAAAGCAGAUGUCAGGCUUUGGUGUGCCUGUGACCACCUCAUUGCUCCCAUAUUAUCCCCCAUUUUUAGUAGAGACGGGGUUUUAGUAGAGACUUGGCCUCCCAGAACCCCCUUCCUCUGCUCCUCCAUGAAUGACAAUUCCAGGCCUCCCCUACCUCAUGUCCUCUCAUUUGGGGGAUUGCUCCGUGCUGUCCCUUUCUCUCAAGGCCGAAGUUGGGAAGUGAGAAACCAUGUUUUUAACUUGUGGCUGCUUUUGCUGCUGCUGCUCCUCCGUAUCUGGCUGUAUGGGUGGAGAACCCACCCCCUGCCCACCACAGGGGUCUCCUUCCAGGCCACUCAGGACAUUUUUAGCUUCUCUCCUCCCCAUGUUCCCUUUUUUCUCUAAAGUCCCCUGACAUCAGCCCUCCCAACUCCUAAGAGGGACUACCCAUGAGAGUGGGGUUCUGAGGCUCCCCUAUGGGGACAGUUCCGUUCUUGAAGUGUCAGUGUUGGGGAAUAUCUGUGGCCUAUGAGGCCCAUCUCAGGUUUGGGGAUCCCCCAGUCCCUAUGAUCAGUGUUGGAGUACCCCCCUGGGAGAGCCUAGUUUCUUUGAGGCCCCAGGCCCUCUUUUAACUACCUUUGAAUAGGUGUUAUCCCUGUAUUUAUGGAAAUAAAGUUCCAUUUCCUCA